AGAGGAACCUAGGACGCUCCAGGAAUCGGGUGUGCCUGGCCCUGGCCGGGGGCUGCCCCCGGGAGCAGCGUCCAGGCCCAUGGCGGAUGCAGUCUAGAGGACUGCCUGGAGGAGGCGGCGCCGGGGCGAGACCUCCAGAGCGCAAGGCCGGCGGGAGAAAAGCUGAGGAAGUGGGAAAUCUGUGGCUGGAGCUCAGCAGAUUGCAACACUUCUACAUCAAGAAAAUGUGGCAAUAAGGCUGCCAAACCCUCCUGUCUUCUGAACCGAAUCCUUGUAGAUUCUGGAUAUCGCACCUUCAUAGGAAUAUUCUGAGAAUAUUUUCUCCUAUUCGCUUCCAGGAGCCGUCGUAGCAGCCGAUUAGGACUGGCUGCUGGUGUGGUGAUGACCUAGAGGGCUUCUCCCAGUUUAAGCAAUCAACAAAACCACCGCUCCAGCACUGAUUUGUAGCAUUUGCGGGUUUCCCCCGUGUGACUUCCGCAGGACUGCCAAGUUCAAGCCGCCAGGGCCAGGGCACUGCUAGCAGCUGGGCUGAGCCCUGUUCUCCCGGCGUUCCCACCGCCCAGUGGCAAUAGCUGUGAACGGCGGCAGGAGCAUGGCAGUGGAACAAUAAGGAAAAGAUCUUUUAAAAAAAAGAUAUAAUACAGAAGCCAAGCAAGGCGGCCCCGACCUGUAACCCCAGCACUCUGGGAGGCAGAGGCGGGCGGGCGGAUCGCUUGAGCCCAGGAGUUUGAGACCAGCCUGGCCAACAUAGGAAGGCCUCGUCAAAAAGACAAAAGGGUAAAACGAAUUUAAUAAAAUGAAGUUUAACUUUUACUCAUGUUUGUAUCUAAUGACAAGCUUUUAAAACUGAAAAGUUCACUACUGGCUCCUGCCUGGCGGCUCCAGCCCGACUGGGGGCCGGGGCCUCCCUGCACUGUGGGGUCACGAGUGCCCCUGGACAGCUCCCGAGCGCCCUCCGACCCGCAUGCUCAGCGCAGCCCCGUCGGCGGCGCGCCACGGGCAGAGCGGGCUCAGCGGGGGACGGAAGCUCAGCGCUGCGACCGGGAUCCCGCAGGCUCGCUCCGCAGGGCCGCGGCUCCUCUCCGUGCAGGUGCUGGGCCCGCGGGGGCGGGGCGUCCACACGGUCCGCGCCGAGACCCAAGCGGGGAAAAAGCGAAGAGCGGACAGCGGGGCAGGUGCCACAGGGAGCCUCCGCCCCACCGCGCGAGCAGCAAGUCUGCGGCGCUUGACACCUGCACUGCGAAUGCCAGGCCGCAGCCCGGGCUCCCAAGACGCGAAUACGCGCGCCUGCUCGUGACGUCAUUUUUUGCGGUCUUCCCGAGAGCCAGCAGAGGGCGCCGCCAUGAUGUUUUACGGAAGCCGAUAGUCCUUGCUCAGCGGCACCCCGUCCUUCCGGCUCUCGGCUUUGCCACAAAGCUUCCCGAAGACGCGGCCGCUACCCGGAGACGCGGUCGCCACCCAGAAGCGCUCUCCCGGGAAGCCCCGCUCGUGGGACCGCGCCACCUGCGCCGCCUCUGCGGCCCGCAGCCCGACGGGCGCCGCCAUGUUGGGGUCCUAGCGAGGGACGCGUAG